CCGGAGCGGGGAUCACCUCAACUUGACUGUGGUCCCCCAGCCCUCCAAGAAAUGCCCAUAAACCAAGGAGGAGAGGGUAAAAAAUAGAAGAAUACAUGGAAUUGGGGAGAAGAAUGGGAAAAAAGAUGGGAGUGACUGCAUAAUGUCAGCAUUUUGUGCUUUUGGCUCAGCAUUUGGAUUGGAUGGAGGAUUUUCAUCCUGAAACCAGCCCUCCGUCGCCACCGACCAUGGAAUAAUUGUCUUCCACGAAACUCUUCCCUGGUGCCAAAAAGGGUUUUAUGUAUAUAUUUGAGAGCUCCACAUCCCUGGAUCUGAAUCCUCCACUUCCCACUGGAACCAUGCCCCUCCCAGUCCCGUUUCUCCCCUCUAGGGGAUGGAGGCUGAGAGACCCCAGGAAGAAGAGGAUGGUGAGCAGGGCCCCCCUCAGGAUGAGGAAGGCUGGCCCCCUCCAAACUCCACCACUCGGCCUUGGCGAUCUGCUCCUCCAUCCCCUCCUCCUCCAGGGACCCGCCACACAGCCCUGGGACCCCGCUCGGCCUCCCUGCUCUCCCUGCAGACUGAACUCCUUCUGGACCUGGUGGCUGAAGCCCAGUCCCGCCGCCUGGAGGAGCAGAGGGCCACCUUCUACACCCCCCAAAACCCCUCAAGCCUAGCCCCUGCCCCACUCCGUCCUCUCGAGGACAGAGAACAGCUUUACAGCACUAUCCUCAGUCACCAGUGCCAGCGGAUGGAAGCCCAGCGGUCAGAGCCUCCCCUCCCUCCAGGGGGGCAAGAGCUCCUGGAGUUGCUGCUGAGAGUUCAGGGUGGGGGUCGAAUGGAGGAGCAAAGGUCCCGGCCCCCCACACACACCUGCUGAGACUUGAGCCCCAACCAGCCCUUCCUUGCCACUGGUCUCAAAGCUGGGCAGCCCAUUGCAUGCCCUCAACUCUUGCUUGGCAGGGGUACCAGAGACUGAAAGACACGGCACAAAUCUCAAUAUUCAUCUCCCACAUCACCUUCCCUGGGAACUGGACAGGGUGAAAGUCCUCAAACUCUGGGAACAGGCGAGAUGGAACAGGGAUUUAACUCCCCGCCCACAGGUCCAUGGGAGCUUGAGGCAGUAAGGGGGAUCCCAGGCACCCAUCUCAAGGAGUGGCUGGGAGUCUUUUCCCUAACUUGUGGGGACACCACCAGUUGUCAAGCUACUAGGCAGUAGGGUCUGAGGGCUCAGGCCUCCACCUGAGAGGUUAUAACCUGAGAGACAGCUCUACCCUUCCUCCCAGUAAGAAGGGAAGGUGGGUGGGCACCUGAGAGAUUAAGACUAUUCUCCCAGUCCCACUACCAGCACCCCCGAUCCCUGAGACUGAGGGGUUUACGGGCUGUGAAUGGACCUUCAGCCCUGCCCACCCUCCCUCCCCACUGCUGCUGAGUCUGUCUGAUGUUUUGGUUGUGUGAAUAAAUAUAAUUCCCCUCUGGA